ACUUGCUGCUUUGCCGGGGUGCUGUAUCACCUACGGGCCAGGGCCUGGGUCGAAUUGGUAGGAUUUCUGACUCUGGUAGCUUGACCUUGCCUCCCUGGAGCUCUUCCCAGCUCAGAACAACAGUUGUCACAAAUAACUCCUGUUUGUGAGCACCUGAGGUUUGCUAGAGCCUGACAGUAGCAAGAGGAAGGAACCUAAGACAGGGCAUUGAGGUCAGGAUGGUUGGAUCAAAAGGCAGGCAGAGACGGAAGAGGAGGACUAGAAAUGGCAGUUACAGAAUGUGAAAGGAGAAGGGCUUUGUGAGUGGGGAGGAGAGUUGUUGAAAGUGUAAUGGCUUUGGGUUUAGGAAUGGAGACUAAAGCUAGAAUGCAGAGGGAAGGGAUCGGGGCUGUGUGAGUGUAAACUCAUUCAGGGAUUGAGAAAAGGGAAGGGUUGUGAAAUGCCAGAGGGCACAGUGGAAUUUGGCUGUACAGAAAGGGGGGAAAUGGGACAGAGUCCCCUAGUCUGAGAGACUUAGCUGUCUGGUGAGAGACUCAGGGUUAGUCACAUGGUCAUCUGAGGAGUGGCUACAUCUGUCUAGUUUCCAAUUGUUUUCCAGCACCUAGCACAGUGUCUGUCACACAGAAAAGGCUUAAUAAAUAUCUACUGAUCAAACGUUGAAUUAGUAGGGAGAGGCUGGGGGAAAGAGUUGCCCACCUAAUUUUCACCCACUCCCCCCACCUAAGUCUACAUUAAUGGGCAAACUGGGAAAUCAGAAACCGGAGGGAAUGGCUGGAGGGUAGUUAACCAGUGACAGUGAGAUCUGAGGCAGACAGGAGAGACUGGGUUAGGGUCACACUUGGAGGCAGCCAGGGGAACUCUCAGGGCUCAUGUGCAGAGUCUUUGUAGUGAUAAUUGGAGGAAAACAUGAAUGAACAGCCCUAGGAGCCCAAGAGGAAGAUGUGGAGGAGGGAAGAGAAAGGAGGCGGUUUCCAGAAAAGGUUGAGAGUUGUUUCCAAAGAGAGAGUUGGCAAAUGUGAAUUAAAAGUAGCAUCCCCACCCCAUUCCCAAUCAUGAAACUACAAUUGAAUUGGUCAUAACCGUAUAUAUACAAUGGCCGCAAAUAAGGAGUUCAUAAAUCAAUACCAGACCCAUUCUAAACACCUAUCCCAAGCCAGGUAAUUAUUAAUACAACGAAGGCAGCAUUGGCCAUGUGGGCCAAAAGGCCAAAGGAGGGAGAAGUUACUGCUGCCCAGAUCUUGAUGUAAAGAACCCUGUGAGGGAUGGCCUUGACAUCUGACUCUCCAUUGUUGAAAGACUCCAGAGGGUACUGGCUGUCACGCUGACAUGAGCCCCCAGCACUCCUCCGUCUACCAUGGCCACCCUUAACUCAGCCUCUACCACUGGUACCACCCCCUCCCCUGGGCACAAUGCCCCGUCCCUGCCUUCGGACACCUUCUCCUCCAGCACCCCCUCUGAUCCUGUCACCAAAGAUCCCCCUGCUGCCUCCUCCACCUCUGAGAACAUGAGGUCCUCAGAGCCAGGGGGACAGCUCCUGGAGUCGGGCUGUGGCCUCGUCCCACCAAAGGAGAUUGGGGAGCCCCAGGAAGGGCCUGACUGUGGUCACUUCCCACCAAAUGACCCAGGGGUGGAAAAGGACAAGGAGCAGGAGGAGGAAGAAGAAGGGCUCCCUCCCAUGGACCUAAGCAACCACUUAUUCUUCACAGCUGGAGGUGAGGCCUACCUAGUGGCCAAGCUGUCCCUGCCAGGUGGCAGUGAACUCCUGUUACCAAAGGGCUUCCCCUGGGGUGAGGCGGGCAUCAAGGAAGAGCCCAGUCUGCCCUUCCUUGCCUACCCACCCCCCUCACACCUCACUGCCCUUCACAUCCAACAUGGCUUUGACCCAAUCCAAGGCUUUAGCUCUUCUGACCAAAUUCUGUCCCAUGAUACCUCAGCACCAUCUCCGGCUGCCUGUGAGGAAAGGCAUGGAGCUUUCUGGAGCUACCAGCUGGCUCCAAAUCCACCCGGAGAUCCCAAAGAUGGCCCCAUGGGGAACAGCGGGGGCAACCACGUGGCGGUCUUCUGGCUCUGCCUUCUGUGCCGCCUGGGUUUCAGCAAGCCCCAGGCCUUUAUGGAUCACACACAGUCUCAUGGGGUGAAGCUAACCCCUGCCCAAUAUCAGGGCCUGUCAGGUAGCCCAGCUGUACUCCAGGAGGGAGAUGAAGGCUGCAAGGCCCUCAUAAGCUUUCUGGAGCCAAAACUCCCUGCUCGCCCCUCUUCUGACAUACCCCUUGACAACAGCAGCACAGUGAACAUGGAGGCGAAUGUGGCCCAGACAGAGGAUGGCCCCCCUGAGGCAGAAGUCCAGGCCCUUAUCCUCCUGGAUGAAGAAGUUAUGGCCCUCAGCCCACCCUCUCCACCCACAGCCACCUGGGACCCCAGCCCAACCCAAGCCAAAGAAUCGCCAGUAGCAGCAGGCGAGGCAGGGCCAGAUUGGUUCCCUGAGGGGCAAGAAGAGGAUGGAGGGCUCUGCCCCCCACUCAACCAAAGCUCACCCACCUCCAAGGAGGGGGGCACUCUCCCUGCCCCAGUGGGCUCCCCCGAAGACCCCAGUGACCCACCCCAGCCCUAUCGCCUAGCUGAUGACUACACCCCAGCCCCUGCAGCCUUCCAGGGCCUCAGCCUGUCCAGCCACAUGUCCCUGCUCCACUCACGCAACUCCUGCAAGACACUCAAGUGUCCCAAGUGCAACUGGCACUACAAGUACCAGCAGACCCUGGAUGUGCACAUGCGAGAGAAGCACCCUGAGAGCAACAGUCACUGCAGCUACUGCAGUGCUGGGGGCGCCCACCCCCGCCUUGCUCGUGGAGAGAGCUACAACUGUGGCUACAAACCCUACCGCUGUGACGUCUGCAACUACUCUACAACCACCAAAGGCAACCUCAGCAUCCAUAUGCAGUCUGACAAGCACCUGGCCAACCUACAGGGCUUCCAGGCGGGCCCUGGUGGGCAGGGAAGUCCACCAGAGGCAUCACUCCCACCCUCCGCGGGAGACAAAGAGCCUAAGACCAAAUCAUCCUGGCAGUGCAAGGUGUGCAGCUACGAGACAAACAUCUCCCGUAACCUGCGCAUCCAUAUGACCUCUGAGAAGCACAUGCAGAAUGUCCUAAUGCUGCACCAGGGGCUGCCGCUGGGCCUGCCACCUGGAUUGAUGGGGCCAGGCCCUCCUCCCCCACCAGGGGCUACCCCCACUAGCCCCCCUGAACUCUUCCAGUACUUUGGGCCCCAGGCCCUAGGGCAGCCUCAGACUCCCUUGGCUGGCCCGGGGCUGAGGCCAGACAAGCCCCUGGAAGCCCAGCUACUUCUCAAUGGUUUCCACCACGUAGGAGCACCUGCCCGCAAGUUCCCCACAUCCGCCCCUGGAAGCCUAUCCCCUGAUGCCCACCUGCCUCCAAGUCAGCUCCUGGGUUCCUCAUCUGACAGCCUGCCCACCUCACCACCCCCAGACGACAGCCUGUCCCUGAAGGUGUUCCGCUGCCUAGUGUGCCAGGCCUUCAGCACAGACAGCCUGGAGCUGCUGCUCUACCACUGCAGCAUAGGCCGGAGCCUCCCGGAAGCUGAAUGGAAGGAGGUGGCUGGUGACACCCACCGCUGCAAGCUUUGCUGCUAUGGCACCCAGCUCAAGGCCAACUUCCAACUCCACCUCAAGACUGACAAACAUGCUCAGAAGUACCAGCUGGCAGCCCACCUGCGGGAGGGGGGUGGAGCCAUGGGCACCCCUUCCCCAGCAUCCCUGGGAGAUGGGGCUCCUUAUGGGUCUGUCUCCCCACUACACCUGCGCUGCAACAUCUGUGACUUUGAGUCCAACAGCAAGGAGAAGAUGCAGCUGCAUGCCAGGGGUGCAGCCCACGAAGAAAACAGCCAAAUCUAUAAGUUUCUGCUGGACAUGGAGGGAGCGGAGGCAGGGGCAGAGCUGGGGCUAUACCACUGCCUGUUGUGUGCGUGGGAGACACCCUCCCGCUUGGCUGUGCUGCAACACCUGCGCACACCUGCCCACCGCGAUGCCCAGGCCCAGAGGCGUCUGCAGCUGCUACAGAAUGGCCCAACCACUGAGGAAGGACUCGCAGCUCUUCAGAGCAUCCUGAGCUUCAGCCACGGGCAGCUCCGGACUCCCGGGAAGGCUCCUGUCACCCCCUUAGCUGAGCCACCCACCCCUGAGAAAGAUGCCCAGAACAAGACAGAACAAUUGGCUUCAGAAGAGACAGAAAACAAGACUGGCCCUUCCAGAGACAGUGCCAACCAGACCACGGUCAGAAUUGGGGUAUACUGCUGUCCAUACUGCAGCUUCCUGAGCCCAGAGUCCAGCCAGGUGAGGGCUCAUACACUCUCCCAGCAUGCAGUGCAGCCCAAGUACAGAUGCCCACUGUGCCAGGAACAGCUGGUGGGCCGGCCUGCCCUGCACUUCCACCUUAGCCACCUUCACAACGUGGUGCCCGAGUGCGUUGAGAAGCUGCUGCUUGUAGCUACAACUGUAGAAAUGACAUUUACAACCAAAGUGCUGUCUGCACCCACAUUAAGCCCUCUGGACAAUGGCCAAGAACCCCCCACUCAUGGGCCAGAGCCUACACCGAGCAGAGACCAGGCAGCAGAAGGCCCUAACCUGACCCCAGAAGCCAGUCCAGAUCCUCUUCCUGAGCCUCCCCUGGCCUCAGUUGAGGUCCCAGACAAACCCUCAGGAAGCCCUGGCCAACCCCCUUCUCCAGCCCCAUCUCCAGUCCCUGAACCUGAUGCCCAAGCUGAAGACGUAGCUCCUCCGCCCACCAUGGCUGAGGAGGAAGAGGGGACCACUGGGGAGCUCCGCUCUGCAGAGCCAGCUCCAGCUGACUCUCGCCACCCUCUGACCUAUCGGAAAACCACCAACUUUGCCCUGGACAAGUUUCUCGACCCUGCCCGGCCCUAUAAGUGCACUGUGUGUAAGGAGUCCUUCACCCAGAAGAAUAUUCUGUUGGUUCAUUAUAAUUCUGUCUCCCACCUUCACAAGAUGAAGAAGGCUGCCAUUGACCCCUCUGCCCCUGCACGGGGAGAGGCCGGUGCCCCACCCACCACCACUGCUGCCACAGACAAGCCCUUUAAGUGCACAGUCUGCAGAGUCUCCUACAACCAGAGCUCCACCCUGGAGAUCCACAUGCGGUCAGUUCUGCAUCAGACUCGCUCUCGGGGAACCAAGACUGAUUCCAAGAUUGAAGGGCCAGAACGCAGCCAAGAAGAGCCCAAGGAAGGCGAGACAGAGGGGGAGGUGGGCACUGAGAAGAAGGGCCCUGACACCAGUGGCUUCAUAUCUGGAUUGCCUUUCCUGUCCCCUCCCCCACCUCCCUUGGACCUGCACCGAUUCCCAGCCCCUCUCUUCACCCCACCAGUCCUGCCCCCCUUCCCUCUGGUGCCCGAAUCACUGCUUAAGCUCCAGCAGCAGCAGCUGCUCCUGCCCUUCUACCUCCACGAUCUCAAGGUGGGGCCCAAGCUGACACUAGCUGGGCCUGCACCUGUGCUGUCCCUGCCAGCUGCCACCCCUCCUCCUCCACCCCAACCUCCCAAGGCUGAGCUGGCUGAGCGGGAGUGGGAGCGGCCCCCCAUGGCCAAAGAGGGUAAUGAGGCAGGGCCUUCCUCACCCCCCGACCCAUUGCCCAACGAGGCUGCCCGCACUGCAGCCAAAGCCCUUCUAGAAAACUUUGGCUUUGAGCUGGUGAUCCAGUACAAUGAAGGGAAGCAAGCUGUGCCCCCUCCCCCUACCCCACCCCCACCUGAGGCCCUCGGGGGUGGGGACAAGCUGGCCUGUGGGGCCUGUGGGAAACUCUUCUCCAAUAUGCUUAUCCUCAAGACACACGAGGAACAUGUCCACCGCCGCUUUCUGCCCUUUGAAGCCCUGAGCCGUUAUGCUGCUCAGUUUCGAAAGAGCUAUGACAGCCUAUACCCGCCCCUUGCAGAGCCUCCCAAACCUCCUGAUGGGUCUCUGGAUUCACCUGUUCCCCAUCUGGGCCCACCCUUCCUGGUCCCAGAGCCUGAGGCAGGGGGGACCCGUGCCCCUGAAGAGCGAAGUCGAGCAGGGGGACACUGGCCCAUAGAAGAGGAAGAAAGCUCCAGAGGGAAUCUUCCUCCCCUGGUGCCUGCCGGCCGCCGGUUCUCCAGAACCAAGUUCACAGAGUUCCAGACCCAAGCCCUGCAGUCUUUCUUUGAGACUAGCGCCUACCCCAAAGACGGAGAGGUGGAGCGACUCGCAAGUCUGUUGGGUCUGGCUAGCCGUGUGGUGGUGGUGUGGUUCCAGAAUGCCCGCCAGAAAGCACGCAAAAAUGCCUGUGAGGGUGGGUCCAUGCCAACCGGAGGAGGCACUGGGGGAGCCUCCGGCUGCAGGCGUUGCCACGCCACUUUCUCCUGUGUUUUUGAGUUGGUGCGCCACCUCAAGAAGUGCUAUGAUGACCAGACCCUUGAAGAGGAGGAGGAAGAGGCAGAGAGAGGGGAAGAGGAGGAAGAGGUGGAAGAAGAAGAAGUAGAGGAGGAACAGGGCCUUGAACCUCCAGCAGGGCCUGAGGGCCCAUUACCAGAGCCUCCAGAUGGGGAGGAGCUGAGCCAAGCAGAGGCAACAAAGGCAGGAGGCAAAGAGCCUGAAGAGAAGGCUACUCCAUCACCUUCCCCAGCCCAUACCUGUGACCAGUGUGCCAUUUCUUUCUCCAGCCAGGACCUCCUGACCAGUCACCGCCGACUACAUUUCCUGCCAUCUCUGCAGCCCAGUGCUCCCCCCCAACUCCUAGAUCUGCCCUUGCUGGUGUUUGGGGAGAGAAACCCCCUGGUGGCAGCCACCUCACCAAUGCCAGGUCCACCUCUCAAACGGAAGCAUGAGGACGGCAGCUUGUCUCCCACAGGCAGUGAAGCAGGGGGAGGAGGGGAGGGCGAGCCCCCCAGGGACAAGCGCCUGCGCACCACCAUCUUGCCUGAGCAGCUAGAGAUCCUGUACCGUUGGUACAUGCAGGAUUCCAACCCAACACGCAAGAUGCUCGACUGCAUCUCCGAGGAGGUGGGGCUCAAAAAGCGAGUGGUACAGGUCUGGUUCCAGAAUACCAGGGCCCGGGAGAGGAAAGGCCAGUUUCGAAGCACCCCUGGGGGGGUGCCUAGUCCAGCAGUGAAACCGCCUGCCACAGCCACCCCUGCAUCCUUGCCCAAGUUCAACCUCUUAUUAGGCAAGGUAGAUGAUGGCACUGGGAGGGAAGCCCCAAAGAGGGAAGCACCUGCUUUUCCCUACCCCACUGCCACGCUUGCUUCUGGGCCCCAGCCUUUCCUACCACCUGGGAAAGAGGCCACCACCCCAACACCAGAGCCACCUCUACCUCUCCUACCUCCCCCUCCACCCAGUGAGGAAGAGGGCCCAGAGGAACCACCUAAAGCUUCUCCAGAGAGUGAGGCUUGCAGUCUCUCUGCAGGAGAUCUGAGUGAUUCAUCUGCUUCCAGCCUAGCUGAACCAGAAUCCCCUGGGGCUGGAGGGACCAGUGGGGGACCUGGAGGUGGGACUGGGGUUCCAGAUGGAAUGGGGCAGCGGCGCUACAGGACCCAGAUGAGCAGCCUGCAGCUGAAGAUCAUGAAAGCCUGCUAUGAAGCUUACCGCACCCCCACCAUGCAGGAGUGUGAGGUGCUGGGAGAGGAGAUUGGGCUGCCCAAGAGAGUCAUCCAGGUCUGGUUCCAGAAUGCUCGUGCCAAGGAAAAGAAGGCCAAACUACAGGGGACAGCCGCUGGGAGCACUGGGGGCAGCAGUGAGGGCCUCUUAGCAGCCCAGCGCACUGACUGCCCCUAUUGUGAUGUCAAGUAUGAUUUCUAUGUCUCCUGCCGAGGCCAUCUCUUUUCCCGUCAGCACCUGGCCAAGCUCAAGGAGGCGGUUCGAGCCCAGCUGAAGAGUGAAAGCAAGUGCUACGACUUGGCCCCAGCACCUGAGGCUCCCCCAGCUCUCAAGGCCCCACCUGCCACCACACCUGCCUCCAUGCCCCUCGGGGCUGCCCCAACCUUGCCUCGCCUGGCGCCGGUCCUCUUAUCUGGCCCAGCUCUGGCUCAGCCCCCGCUGGGCAACUUAGCUCCUUUCAAUUCAGGCCCGGCAGCCUCCUCAGGCCUCCUCGGCCUCGCCACUUCGGUCCUGCCUACCACCACAGUGGUCCAGACUGCUGGCCCAGGCCGCCCCUUACCUCAGAGACCCAUGCCCGACCAAACCAACACCUCCACAGCAGGCACCACUGACCCUGUCCCAGGCCCUCCUACUGAGCCCUUGGGGGACAAGGUCUCCAGUGAGCGAAAGCCAGUUGCAGGCCCCACCAGCUCCUCCAAUGAUGCCCUCAAGAACCUCAAAGCAUUGAAGACCACUGUCCCAGCCCUGUUGGGGGGCCAGUUCCUGCCCUUUCCAUUGCCCCCUGCUGGGGGAACAGCACCGCCAGCUGUCUUUGGCCCCCAGCUACAGGGGGCCUACUUCCAACAGCUCUAUGGCAUGAAGAAGGGGCUAUUUCCCAUGAACCCCAUGAUACCUCAGACCCUCAUUGGGCUGCUCCCCAAUGCCCUCCUCCAGCCGCCACCCCAGCCCCCUGAGCCCACAGCCACAGCACCUCCAAAGCCUCCUGAACUGCCUGCUCCAGGGGAGGGGGAAGCUGGUGAGGUUGAUGAGCUGCUGACAGGCAGCACUGGCAUCUCCACCGUGGAUGUAACCCAUCGCUACCUGUGCCGCCAGUGCAAGAUGGCAUUUGACGGGGAGGCCCCGGCUACUGCCCACCAGAGAUCCUUCUGCUUCUUUGGGCGGGGCUCUGGGGGCUCCAUGCCACCCCCAUUGCGGGUGCCCAUCUGCACCUACCACUGCCUGGCAUGUGAGGUGCUGCUGAGUGGGCGUGAAGCCCUAGCCUCCCACCUGCGCUCCUCGGCCCACAGGCGCAAGGCAGCCCCACCUCAAGGGGGCCCACCCAUCUCCAUCACCAACGCCGCCACUGCUGCCUCGGCUGCUGUGGCUUUUGCCAAAGAGGAAGCAAGAUUACCUCACACGGACUCCAACCCAAAAACUACGACUACCUCUACACUUCUAGCUUUAUAAACAGAUUAACCAAGAUGGGGAGAGGGGAGGGCCUCAGGGCUCCCUCUUUUACCCCAAGGGGUGUUCGGUGGGAGCUCAAAUCCCUCACCCCACCCCCUGGCCCCGCCCACCUCACAGGAACUGUUCAGUUCCCACCCUCAGUGGGCACCACACACCCCACUUCCAGCAGAGUCCUGCCUCCUCCCAAUCCCCACAGACACACACAUUGAUCCUCCUCCUCAGCUCCUUGCAGAUGUAGCCCUUGCCCAUCUUCACAGACACAUACACCCAUCUUGGCACCCUGAUUAUUCAUACAUGUCUGCCUACCACACACAAAAUAUAUCCUUGGUUCUAUCUUCCUUUUCCUCACUGAAUUCCCAGCUCCCCAUCCCCAUAAAUGCAUACACAUACAUGCACACACACACGUUAUCCCAUGAUGUUCCACUGAGAAAACACCAAAAAAUUUUGAAAAAGAAGAUAAAAAGAAGAAACGAAAAAGAAAGCCCAAGGCAAAGAAGGGGGAAGGAAAACAAACUUCGCCACUCUCUCUUCUCCUUCCUAACCCUUUGUCUAGAGCACCACACCGCUCACAAACUCUUUCCAAAUGCUCAGUUGGCUCCCAAAGUUGGAGCCUGGCAUGGGCAGGGAGCCCACAAAACUCUAACCAAACUGGAGGCUGGCAUGGGAGAAGUGCUUCUGGUUCACUCUUCCUACCCUCUCCCUCCUAACCCUCUCCUUGCCUGACAGGGGAGCCCCUGUGGCCUGGACUCUAGGGGAUGCCGCCACCAGAAACCCCUCUGCCAAUCCCUACCUUGCACCCUGGGAACUGCAGUAACUUAUUCUCAAAGGCUUUAAACACAGAGAUCCUCUCAGCGGCCGUGGGCCUGCCCCUUGUCCUAGCCCUGCCACGUGAGGGUCCAGCCUCCAGGGACAGGCACUGCCCACCAACGGCAAAUCCAAAGUUCUUUCAAAAAAAAAAACUGAAACACAACCAAAAAAGCAAGAGCGAGAGAGAGUACGUGCACACGCGCACAAAAGAGAGAAACGGACACCAGAGGAAUGAACUAAAGAAAAACGUAAACUUGGAAAAUACAGAAAAAAAAAAAAAGGAAGAAAACUCCCAUCA